GGUGGCCGGGCGGGACCAACAAAGAUGGCGGCGGCCCCUGCGGCGGGAGCGAUCUGGGCAACGGCUGCGGCUAAAGCUGCAGCCGGGCCCACGGGGGGGCUGCACGGGGGUAGUAGGGGGUGGCCCUGAACUGGGGCCUGGCCCUGGCUGGCCUCUCCCGCCGCCUCACUGGGGGACAGGUACGGGCCGGGGCGUUAUGGCAUGGCGGGGUGUGGGGGGGCGCAGAGGGAAGACUGCUCCAGACCCGAGAGGACACUCUCCACAAAGGCGCGUGGGGCCCGGCGGGGCCUGGGAGAACUGGGCUGGAGGGACAGCAUCCCUGGACCGCGGGGAAUACGCCGCCGGAUUCCGUAGCCAAUCAGCGGUCUCGGCCUUUCUGCCCUCGAGGGGGGCGGACCCGGCUAAAGCCCUGCUGUGGUGGGAGAAGUGCAGAGAUUAAGGGUCAAGGAGUUGUUCGUCCUCCAUCCCCGACUACUGCUUUCUGAACCUCGACACCAUGUCGGAGGUCGGAGGUGGGGGAGGGAAUGGAUCGUAAGUCACCCAUAUAGUCUGCUUCAUUUGCAGCCCAGAGAGGCAGGGAUUCGAGGAUGGAGGGCUGUCUUUUGGGCUGUUAUUCUUGCAUCUACACUACCAUUUGGCUAGGGUCUUAAGUGACCCGAGGCACAUCCUACUUUACUAGCCGGGUAUGGGGUCCCAUGUUACGUUAGAGCCGAGAUAGGAGUUAUCACUGGCUUUUCAGUAAAGAUGUGUUCUGCAGGGAGGGGUCGGGAGUAUAGAAAGGGUCAAAGCCAUGGGCUGCUUAUCUUUCAUUCAUUUGUUUACCCAAUAGAUACUAAGUAUUUACUUUGUACCAAACACGAUGCCAGGUACUGGGGAUACGAUGGCUGAUUCGAUAGAUCUGGUUCCUGCCCUCAGUGCGUAUACUGCUCCCCACUUUCGUUGAUGUGGUAGUGGUGAUGACUGAGCCAACCACCUAAUGUGGAAAUGAGAGGACAGCAAGAUUGUGGGUAUGGAAUGGGGCAAAGCAAUAAGGGAAAAUUAGUGUGGCAGGGUUCAGUACAGCAGCCUGGGUUCCCAUUUCCCCCCAUAUUCAAAUGCUGACACUCUCUUCUCCUCCCAGGUCCAGCCUGUGGUGUCCACAAUGCCCCAGGCCUCUGAGCACCGCCUGGGCCGUACCCGAGAGCCACCUGUUAAUAUCCAGCCCCGAGUGGGAUCCAAGCUACCAUUUGCCCCCAGGGCCCGCAGCAAGGAGCGCAGAAACCCAGCCUCUGGGCCAAACCCCAUGUUACGACCUCUGCCUCCCCGGCCAGGUCUGCCUGAUGAACGGCUCAAGAAACUGGAGCUGGGACGGGGACGGACCUCAGGCCCUCGUCCCAGAGGCCCCCUUCGAGCAGAUCAUGGGGUUCCCCUGCCUGGCUCACCACCCCCAACAGUGGCUUUGCCUCUCCCAUCUCGGACCAACUUAGCCCGUUCCAAGUCUGUGAGCAGUGGGGACUUGCGUCCAAUGGGGAUUGCCUUGGGAGGGCACCGUGGCACCGGAGAGCUUGGGGCUGCACUGAGCCGCUUGGCCCUCCGGCCUGAGCCACCCACUUUGAGACGUAGCACUUCUCUCCGCCGCCUAGGGGGCUUUCCUGGACCCCCUACCCUGUUCAGCAUACGGACAGAGCCCCCUGCUUCCCAUGGCUCCUUCCACAUGAUAUCCGCCCGGUCCUCUGAGCCUUUCUACUCUGAUGACAAGAUGGCUCAUCACACACUCCUUCUGGGCUCUGGUCAUGUUGGCCUUCGAAACCUGGGAAACACGUGCUUCCUGAAUGCUGUGCUGCAGUGUCUGAGCAGCACUCGACCUCUUCGGGACUUCUGUCUGAGAAGGGACUUCCGGCAAGAGGUGCCUGGAGGAGGCCGAGCCCAAGAGCUCACUGAAGCCUUUGCAGAUGUGAUUGGUGCCCUCUGGCACCCUGACUCCUGCGAAGCUGUGAAUCCUACUCGAUUCCGAGCUGUCUUCCAGAAAUAUGUUCCCUCCUUCUCUGGAUACAGCCAGCAGGAUGCCCAAGAGUUCCUGAAGCUCCUCAUGGAGCGGCUACACCUUGAAAUCAACCGCCGAGGCCGCCGGGCUCCACCGAUACUUGCCAAUGGUCCAGUUCCCUCUCCACCCCGCCGAGGAGGGGCUCUGCUAGAAGAACCUGAGUUAAGUGAUGAUGACCGAGCCAACCUAAUGUGGAAACGUUACCUGGAGCGAGAGGACAGCAAGAUUGUGGACCUGUUUGUGGGCCAGUUGAAAAGUUGUCUCAAGUGCCAGGCCUGUGGGUAUCGCUCCACGACCUUCGAGGUUUUUUGUGACCUGUCCCUGCCCAUCCCCAAGAAAGGAUUUGCUGGGGGCAAGGUGUCUCUGCGGGAUUGUUUCAACCUUUUCACUAAGGAAGAAGAGCUAGAGUCGGAGAAUGCCCCAGUGUGUGACCGAUGUCGGCAGAAAACUCGAAGUACCAAAAAGUUGACAGUACAAAGAUUCCCUCGAAUCCUCGUGCUCCAUAUCCUAAUCUUCAGAUUCUUACUUCUCUUAGGAUACCUCCCAUACAUUCUCUUUCCUCCAUGUUUCCAGAGAAUUGAAUUUUCCUUAGGAAAAGUCUGCCACCCACUUUUCCACAAGAUGCUCCCAGUGUGUCGGGAGUGGGGAGAGGACAGCUUUCAGGAUAGAAGAAGUUCCCCUCAGAGGCCCACUGCCUCCCAAAUGCUCCUUAACCAGGGCUUAGAUCUGAAUCGAUUUUCUGCCUCCCGAGGCUCCAUCAAAAAAAGUUCAGUAGGUGUAGACUUUCCACUGCAGCGACUGAGCCUAGGGGACUUUGCCAGUGACAAAGCCGGAAGUCCUGUAUACCAGCUGUAUGCCCUUUGCAACCACUCAGGCAGCGUCCACUAUGGCCACUACACAGCCCUGUGCCGGUGCCAGACUGGUUGGCAUGUCUACAAUGACUCUCGUGUCUCCCCUGUCAGUGAAAACCAGGUGGCAUCCAGCGAGGGCUACGUGCUGUUCUACCAACUGAUGCAGGAGCCACCCCGGUGCCUGUGACACCUCUAAGCUCUGGCACCUGUGAAGCCCUUUAAACACCCUUAAGCCCCAGGCUCCCCGUUUACCUCAGAGACGUCUAUUUUUGUGUCUUUUUAAUCGGGGAGGGGGGAGGGGGUGGUUGUAGCUCCAUUAUUUUUUUUAUUAAAAAAUACCCUUCCACCUGGAGGCUCCCUUGUCUCCCAGCCCCAUGUACAAAGCUCACCAAGCCCCUGCCCAUGUACAGCCCCCAGACCCUCUGCAAUAUCACUUUUUGUGAAUAAAUUUAUUAAGAAAAAA